ACGCCUGUCGUGGUUUAGCUGAACUGAGCUGAAAUCCUAAAGGCCGCGGAGUCGGCGGUGUUGUAGGUAGCGGUACCUUGAGUGGCAACAGAAUUCGAUUAAAUUACAAUGGGAAACAUUUUUGAAAAGCUCUUUAAAAGUCUACUUGGGAAAAAAAAGAUGCGGAUUCUUAUAUUGAGUUUGGAUACAGCUGGAAAAACCACCAUCUUGUAUAAAUUGAAGCUGGGGGAGACUGUGCCUGCCGUCCCUACAGUAGGUUUCUGUGUGGAGACAGUAGAAUAUAAAAAUAACACCUUCGCUGUCUGGGAUGUUGGCAGCCACUUCAAAAUCAGACCUCUGUGGCAGCAUUUUUUCCAGAACACAAAAGGUGCCAGAAGCCCAGGAAGCACACAUCAAGGCUCACUUGCCAGCGGGGUGCUGCCAAUAAAAUGUAGUCACGUGGAAUUUGGAAUGUGGAAAGGAGGUAGAAGUCAUCCUUUCCUCCCCCAUAGCAGCAGGUGUGCAGGCUCUGGUGGUCAGCUGGACUCCAUACUCCCCCACCAGUCACCAGCCUGGGGACCGUGGGGCUGCAAGGACCUCAGCAGCGGUUUCCCAAGUUUCCUGACUUCUUCCAUCCUCUGGAAAUCAGCUGUGGUAAAGUAGCCUGAAAGCCAGUGGUGCAACCCCAUCCCCACAACCUUCACCACCUCUAGCACCUCCAGUGAUAAGCACUAAUUGCCUAUAUACAACCCUUUUUUGUUUGAAAUAUCUAGAGUAAUUUCUGUUUUCCUAUCUGGGGUAGUGUAACAUAAGAAGAAAUAUAUAUUUGGUCUCUGCCCCCAGUUCCUAACACAAAGCUCCUAAAACCCUUGGAAAUUCCUGAAUGAUGGCGGUGCUAAGAGCAUUGUCCUUUGUUAAUUUAUCAUUUUUCUUUUCUCCUAGGUGUUUUUUCCUUUUUAAACUUUUCUUUUAGGUUAGGGGGUACAUAUGCACGUUCGUUAUAUAGCUAAACUUGUGUCAUGGGGGUUUGUUGUACAGAUUAUUUCAUCACCCAGGUACCAAGCCUAGUACCCAAUAGUUUUUUCUGCUCCUCUCCCUCCUCCCACCCUCCACCCUCAGGUAGGGCCCAGUGUCUGUUGUUUAUGAGUUCUCAUCAUUUUGCUCCCACUUAAAAGAACAUACAGUAUUUGGUUUUCUGUUCCUGUCUUAGUUUGCUGAGGAUAAUGGCCUCUAGCUCCAUCUGUGUUCCUGCAAAAGACAUGAUCUCGCUGUUUUUUAUGGUUGCACAUCUUUUGUUCUAACAUUUGGUCCUUAAACCUGGUUCCUGACACAGAGCUCCUAAAUCCCUUGGAAUUUUCUGGGUGAUAGAAGCGUCCUUUGUUCUCAUGAGGUGACUCUUGGUGGGCUCCUUAUUUGGGGACUGGUCACCAAAAAGACCUAUGGUUGGAAGCGUUGUGCUGUCAGCCCCAUUCCCCAUCCUCUGGCGUGGGGAGUAGAGCUGGAGCUCAAUCAUGCCUACGUGAUAAAGCCUCCAGAAAACUCCUUAAAAGACAGGACUUGGAGAGCUUCCGGGUUGGCGAACACAUCCAUGUUCCAGGAGAGUGGUGCACCCCAACUCCACAAGGACCCUUCCAAACCUCACCCUGUGUAUCUCUUCAACUGGCUUCAUCAUUUGUGUCCUUUAAAAUAUCCUUUGUAAUAAAUCAGCACUAGUAAGAAAACUGUUUUCCUGGGUUCCAUGAGCUGUUCUAGCAAAUGUUCAAACCUGAGGAGGGAGUUGUGGGGACCUCCAAUUUACAGCCAGUUGGUCAGAUGCAUAGGUGAUGCUUGGCCUUGCACCUGGGGUCUGACAUGCGGAUGGUCCUGUGUGACUGAGCCCUUAACCUGUGGAGUCUGGUGCUCACUCUGCUUAGGGCUUCUCUUGCCUUUUUAGUGUCCUUCUAGGCGGCCUUUCCUUCCUCUUGUCAGCUCAGAAAACUUUUCUUCCACUUCCCUUCUUCUAAACCAUCCCUUACAUCUACUCCUUUCCAGCCGACCAAGAGCAGAACCACGGCUGGUUCCACUGCCACCAUGCUGUCCCACACUGUCUCCUCAGGAUGUAUUCAGAUGUCCAGCCCUCCCCCCAGUCUAGGAGCCCCCCCUUUGAGGAAAGGGAUGCUGGCCUAGUCAACUCUUUCCCAGCACCAGGUACAGCAUCUGGCACGUUCCAUCUUUUUCAUGGACUCUCCCCAGGCGGCCUGACCUUCCCUCCUCUGAACCGGUGCAUUUCUUGUCUGCAUCAUGUUUGCCCUAAUCAGAUAUCACCUUAUUUCCUCUUUUAAAAAAUGCUUUGUUUCUCUGGCAGGCUUCAUCGGAAUCACAAUUUUCAUUCAUUUAGUAACUGUUGUUGUUUAUUCUAUGUAUUUUUGCAGGAGGCCUGAGGUGGGCUGUGUUCUCCUCCUAUGGCAGGGCUUCACUCUCCUCCUCCUCCGUUGGGGCUUCGCUGUCCCUGGGAUAAGAAUAACAAUGCCAAGGUUUUCAUUCUUGAAAGGAGCAAUUAAGCUUCUCACCCCCUCCUCAUUUUAGAUGGGAACUGUGAGGGCCCCAUCAUUUACCCAGGGUCCCUGUUGAGGAUCUUGUCCUCAUUAGAUGACUUCUUGUGCAGCUUCCAUGCAUGAUUAUUUAUUCUUGUGGCACUGAGAGGUUUGUACAUAUCUUUAAACCAGAGCGGCUGUCCAAAUGAGGAAAGUCCAUCCUAGAAGAUAGAAAGGGAAAUAUUAAUUUUGCAUGUCCUCUGCUUUCCCUGGCCACAGCAAUGAAUCCUCCAAUGUACCUGACUCUCCCUUCGCGAAGAGCAUCCCCUCCAUGGCAGAAAUCUGAAAAUGCCCCUGGGGAGACACAUGCACAAGACAGUGAGUGAUGCAGCCGUUUCCCACGUAUCUCACAAUGUACUUCUCUGGUCUUAUUAGGACUAAAUGAGUAUCUCAGUCCAUAAUCACAGGGAGAACCACCACCACAGACCACAUACCCGGGGUCUUGAAAAUAAUUCCAUGCAUGUGGGACUUUCAGAAGCUCUCCAUGUCUGCCCAGAAGGGCCCCACAAUAUACUGGGGGGACUUUGUAUGUGGCUCAGCAUGGAGCAGGGGCAGGAUUUUCAGUCCCACUCACUCCCUUGGCCAAGUGCCCUUGUGCAGUGAACAAACUGCACAACCAUGCUGGGCAGAAGCAUUUUAUAUCAGUCCCCUUCGGACUUAGUCUCACAGGCAUCAUUUGAUGGGGGAUGGGAGAUGAAGUGGUUCUUCGUUUUCUAGAUACUUUAUUCUAUAAGUUGGAUCACCUCAAGCAAAUGCGUGAGUGCAGCUAGCCAAGUUCUCUAUCUCACAGUCUUCAUAUGGCUGGCUGUCGCUGAUGAGUGAGUGAGCUACGAAAUCAGCUUAAAGCACAACAUGUUAUUUUUGAAUUUGAAUAAAAUAGGAAAAGGCAGAGUGCAUUGUGUGACCAUGGGGUAAGUAAGACACUCUCCCUUUCUCCUUCUCAGUUUUCCUGUCAUAAAAGGACAAACUACUAUCUAAGGUCUCCGUAGUUAAAAUUCUUUUUUGUUGUUUUUUUUUUAUUUGAGACAGUUUGGCUCAUUCCCCAGGCUGGAGUGCAAUGGUGCUAUCUUGGCUCCCUGCAACCUGCGCCUCCUGGGCUCAAGCAGUUCUCCUGCCUCAGCCUCCCAAGUAGCUGGGAUUACACGCCUGCGCCACCACACCCAGCUAAUUUAGUAUUUUUAGUAGAGAUGGGGUUUCACCAUGUUGGUCAGGCUGGUCACGAGCUCCUAACCUCAAGUGAUCCCAAAGUGCUGUGAUUACAGGCGUGAGCCAUCCUGCCUGGCCUUUCUGGUUAAAAUUCUGUGAGGUUUGCAUAAAAGGAAUAGAGUAGGGGCCCAAAAACCAGUAAGAUGAGAAAAUAGUGUUUCCUCAGUUCUAGGAUCCAGGGGAAAAAAAAAAGAAAUAAAAGAGAAAAUACUGUUUCCUGCCACUUAAGAGGAAGGACUCACAUAUCCUACCUUCCAUCAGCCUUGAAGGAGACAAGUGCCCUCUCUCUCACACCCGGUGGCCUUCCCUUCCCCUUUCCCAGAGCCUCCAAGAAGGCCCCUGGCCUGGCCUGAUGCCCACCAUCAGCAGCAAUAGGCACCAAAACCUUUCUCCUUCCUAUCCCUCCCCACCUCCCGAAAGGGCUGGGGACAGCAGGUGUGUCCUUGUUAGUUCCAUCCAGCUCAGCUUUGGCUGGGGAGCUAAUUUCACUGGAGCCAGGCUAAGCAUUAGGGUAAGUAUUUGUCCUGUCUUGGGCAGUUUCCUCACUGAAAAAUGAGGGCAGAGUUCUAAGCCCUCCUCUAAUUCUAAAAUUCUAAUUAAAACGUCGCGAGACUAGUGGUGCAUGCCUGUAAUCCCAGCUACUCGGGAGGCUGAGGCAGGAGAAUCGCUUGAACCUGGGAAGUGGAGGUUGCCGUGAGCCGAGAUCGUGUCAUUGCACUCCAGCCUGGCAACAAGAGGGAAACUCCGUCUCAAAAGAGAAGAAAAAAAAAAUCACCAGACUAAUAUUUACCUUGAGAAUCCUUCUUCAUCUUCUUGUAAUGACCUUCGGUGACAACAUAUCUGUUUUAGAAGAAAACGCAAUUAAGAUUAUCUAUGACAACAACCACCGUCUCCAAAUCUGUAUUGAUUCCUUUUAUUCAUUAUAAGUCUCAUCUACCUGAUGAGGUAACUUUUUUGAAGACAGGAAUUGUAUGCUGUGUAACACUGCUUUGAUUCUUCCAUAGUUCAGUCAUCCUUGCUAUCUUGCGGGGGAUUGGUUCUAGGAUACCGCCCCCACACCAUACCAGAAUCUGUGGAUGCUCAAUCCCUUACAUAUAAUGGUGUAAUAUUUGCUUAUAACCAACACGCAUCCCCCCUAUACUUUAUUUACUUAGCGACAGGAUUGCCCUCUGUUGCUUACGCUGGAGUGCAGUGUCAUCCUCUGUUACUCAGGAUGGAGUGCGGUGUCACGAUCACAGCUCACUGUAGCCUCAACCUCCUGGGCUCCAGUGAUCCGCCCACCUCAGCCUCUUGAGUAGCUGAGACUACAGGUGCAUACUACCACACCUGGCUAUUUUUUUUUUUAAUUUUUAAUAAAGACAAGGUCUCACUAUGCUGCCCAGGUUGGCCUCCCAAUGUGUUGGGAUUACAAGUGUGAGCCACCAUGCCUGGCCCCAUGUAAUUUAAGUCAUCACUAAUAAAAUGUAUACAUAUUGUACAUUGUU